GCACCCGGGGCCGGUUUCGGCGGCGGGGCGGACGCUCCCUCACUAGCCGGGCGCCCGGGCCGGCCGCCGAGGUUUAGGUGGAGGCUGAGGCUGCCGCGCGCCGCGGGAGGAGCCUCGCCCUCGGCGGCUGAGGCGGCGGCGGCACAGGUGGCGCGGGCCGCGCGCGGGGCGCAGCUCGGGAGCGCUCGGCGCCGGGCGCCGCGGCGGCCCCAGGCUCGCGCCCGCGGCGACAGCCGGCUGAGCGGAGCUGCGGGCGCGGCGGCUGCUCUCUCAGCCCGGCCGGCUGGCGGCGGCGCCCGGAGCCCCGAGGAGCCCGCAGGAGCCCGUGGAGCCCGCGGAGCCGGGCAGGGGGCGCUGCGCUCGCCGAGCUCGGAGGGGCCGCCGGGCCGGGCGCUGCGCACUCGCGUCGGGAGCCGCCUCUCGCCCGCGGCGCUCGCCCCUGCCGCCCGCCAGCAUCCCUUGUCCCGCGGCCGCGCUCAGACAACAAAAGCGGAAGAUGCUGCAGUUGGGCAAGGUCAGGACCUUGCCCUGAAGCCGGGCGGCGCCGCGCACGCCUCUUCCCGGACUGAGGAGCUGUCGCCGGCGGAGGGUGCAUGUUUGCGAGGAAGCCGCCGGGCGCCGCGCCUUUGGGAGCUAUGCCUGUUCCAGACCAGCCUUCAUCAGCCUCAGAGAAGACGAGUUCCCUGAGCCCCGGCUUAAACACCUCCAACGGGGAUGGCUCUGAAACAGAAACCACCUCUGCCAUCCUCGCCUCAGUCAAAGAACAGGAAUUACAGUUUGAAAGGCUGACCCGAGAGCUGGAGGCUGAACGGCAGAUCGUAGCCAGCCAGCUGGAGCGAUGCAAGCUCGGAUCCGAGACUGGCAGCAUGAGCAGCAUGAGUUCAGCAGAAGAGCAGUUUCAGUGGCAGUCACAAGAUGGUCAAAAAGAUAUCGAAGAUGAGCUUACAACAGGUCUCGAGCUGGUGGACUCCUGUAUUAGGUCACUACAGGAAUCAGGAAUACUUGACCCACAGGAUUAUUCUACAGGUGAAAGGCCCAGCCUGCUCUCCCAGAGUGCACUUCAGCUCAAUUCCAAACCUGAAGGGUCUUUCCAGUAUCCGGCCAGCUACCAUAGCAACCAGACCCUGGCCCUGGGGGAAACCACCCCUUCACAGCUCCCGGCCCGAGGCACACAAGCCCGAGCUACGGGCCAGAGCUUCAGCCAGGGCACGACCAGCCGCGCCGGCCACCUGGCGGGGCCCGAGCCCGCGCCGCCGCCGCCGCCGCCGCCGCGGGAGCCGUUCGCGCCCAGCCUGGGCAGCGCCUUCCACCUGCCCGACGCGCCGCCCGCCGCCGCCGCCGCCGCGCUCUACUACUCCAGCUCCACGCUGCCCGCGCCGCCGCGCGGGGGCUCCCCGCUGGCCGCGCCCCAGGGCGGUUCGCCCACCAAGCUGCAGCGCGGCGGCUCGGCCCCCGAGGGCGCCACCUACGCCGCGCCGCGCGGCUCCUCGCCCAAGCAGUCGCCCAGCCGCCUGGCCAAGUCCUACAGCACCAGCUCGCCCAUCAACAUCGUCGUGUCCUCGGCCGGCCUGUCCCCGAUCCGCGUGACCUCGCCCCCCACCGUGCAGUCCACCAUCUCCUCCUCGCCCAUCCACCAGCUGAGCUCCACCAUCGGCACGUACGCCACCCUGUCGCCCACCAAGCGCCUGGUCCACGCGUCCGAGCAGUACAGCAAGCACUCGCAGGAGCUGUAUGCCACGGCCACCCUCCAGAGGCCGGGCAGCCUGGCAGCUGGUUCCCGAGCCUCAUACAGCAGCCAGCAUGGGCACCUGGGCCCAGAGUUGCGGGCCCUGCAGUCCCCAGAACACCACAUAGAUCCCAUCUAUGAAGACCGCGUCUAUCAGAAGCCCCCUAUGAGGAGUCUCAGCCAGAGCCAGGGGGACCCUCUGCCGCCAGCACACACCGGCACCUACCGCACGAGCACAGCCCCAUCUUCCCCUGGUGUCGACUCCGUCCCCUUGCAGCGCACAGGCAGCCAGCACGGCCCACAGAAUGCCGCCGCGGCCACCUUCCAGAGGGCCAGCUAUGCCGCCGGCCCAGCCUCCAAUUACGCGGACCCCUACCGACAGCUGCAGUAUUGUCCCUCUGUUGAGUCUCCAUACAGCAAAUCCGGCCCUGCUCUCCCGCCUGAAGGCACCUUGGCCAGGUCCCCGUCCAUUGAUAGCAUUCAGAAAGAUCCCAGAGAAUUUGGAUGGAGAGACCCGGAACUGCCGGAAGUGAUUCAGAUGUUGCAGCACCAGUUUCCCUCGGUCCAGUCUAACGCGGCAGCCUACUUGCAACACCUCUGUUUUGGAGACAACAAAAUUAAAGCCGAGAUAAGGAGACAAGGAGGCAUCCAGCUCCUGGUGGACCUGUUGGAUCAUCGGAUGACCGAAGUCCACCGUAGUGCCUGUGGAGCUCUGAGAAACCUGGUGUAUGGGAAGGCCAACGAUGAUAACAAAAUUGCCCUGAAAAACUGUGGUGGCAUCCCAGCACUGGUGAGGUUACUCCGCAAGACGACUGACCUGGAGAUCCGGGAGCUGGUCACAGGAGUCCUUUGGAACCUCUCCUCAUGCGAUGCACUCAAAAUGCCAAUCAUCCAGGAUGCCCUAGCAGUACUGACCAACGCGGUGAUUAUCCCCCACUCAGGCUGGGAAAAUUCGCCUCUUCAGGAUGAUCGGAAAAUACAGCUGCAUUCAUCACAGGUGCUGCGUAACGCCACCGGGUGCCUAAGGAAUGUUAGUUCGGCCGGAGAGGAGGCCCGCAGAAGGAUGAGAGAGUGUGAUGGGCUUACGGAUGCCUUGCUGUACGUGAUCCAGUCUGCGCUGGGGAGCAGUGAGAUCGAUAGCAAGACCGUUGAAAACUGUGUGUGCAUUUUAAGGAACCUCUCGUACCGGCUGGCGGCAGAAACGUCUCAGGGACAGCACAUGGGCACGGACGAGCUGGACGGGCUACUCUGUGGCGAGGCCAAUGGCAAGGAUGCUGAGAGCUCUGGGUGCUGGGGCAAGAAGAAGAAGAAAAAGAAAUCCCAAGAUCAGUGGGAUGGAGUAGGACCUCUUCCAGACUGUGCUGAACCACCAAAAGGGAUCCAGAUGCUGUGGCACCCAUCAAUAGUCAAACCCUACCUCACACUGCUCUCUGAGUGCUCAAAUCCAGACACGCUGGAAGGGGCGGCAGGCGCCCUGCAGAACUUGGCUGCAGGGAGCUGGAAGGGCUGGGCUGAGGAUGUGGCAGGCAUGGCAUAUGCCCUACGUUCACUGCCAGAGGGGGCUCCCUGCCUGCCACAGUGGUCAGUAUAUAUCCGAGCCGCUGUCCGAAAAGAGAAAGGCCUGCCCAUCCUCGUGGAGCUGCUCCGAAUAGACAAUGACCGUGUGGUGUGCGCGGUGGCCACUGCGCUGCGGAACAUGGCCUUGGACGUCAGAAAUAAGGAGCUCAUCGGCAAAUACGCCAUGCGAGACCUAGUCCACAGGCUUCCAGGAGGGAACAACAGCAACAACACUGCAAGCAAGGCCAUGUCGGAUGACACAGUGACAGCUGUCUGCUGCACACUGCACGAAGUGAUUACCAAGAACAUGGAGAACGCCAAGGCCUUACGGGAUGCCGGUGGCAUCGAGAAGUUGGUCGGCAUCUCCAAAAGCAAAGGAGAUAAACACUCUCCAAAAGUGGUCAAGGCUGCAUCUCAGGUCCUCAACAGCAUGUGGCAGUACCGAGAUCUGAGGAGUCUCUACAAAAAGGAUGGAUGGUCACAAUACCACUUUGUAGCCUCGUCUUCAACCAUCGAGAGGGACCGGCAAAGGCCCUACUCCUCCUCCCGCACGCCCUCCAUCUCCCCUGUGCGCGUGUCUCCCAACAACCGCUCAGCAAGUGCCCCAGCUUCACCUCGGGAAAUGAUCAGCCUCAAAGAAAGGAAAACAGACUACGAGUGCACCGGCAGCAACGCCACCUACCACGGAGCUAAAGGCGAACACACUUCCAGGAAAGAUGCCAUGACAGCUCAAAACACUGGAAUUUCAACUUUGUAUAGGAAUUCUUAUGGUGCGCCCGCUGAAGACAUCAAACACAACCAGGUUUCAGCACAGCCAGUCCCACAGGAGCCCAGCAGAAAAGAUUACGAGACCUACCAGCCAUUUCAGAAUUCCACAAGAAAUUACGAUGAGUCCUUCUUCGAGGACCAGGUCCACCAUCGCCCUCCCGCCAGCGAGUACACCAUGCACCUGGGUCUCAAGUCCACCGGCAACUACGUUGACUUCUACUCAGCUGCCCGUCCCUACAGUGAACUGAACUAUGAAACGAGCCACUACCCGGCCUCCCCCGACUCCUGGGUGUGAGGAGCAGGGCACAGGCGCUCCGGGAACAGUGCAUGUGCAUGCAUACCACAAGACAUUUCUUUCUGUUUUGUUUUUUUCUCCUGCAAAUUUAGUUUGUUAAAGCCUGUUCCAUAGGAAGGCUGUGAUAACCAGUAAGGAAAUAUUAAGAGCUAUUUUAGAAAGCUAAAUGAAUCGCAAGUUAACUUGGAAAUCAGUAGAAAGCUAAAGUGAUCCUAAAUAUGACAGUGGGCAGCACCUUUCUAGCGUGAGCUGUAGAGUAACGAGAAGUGCUUUAUACUGAACGUGGUUGAUGGGAGGAGAGACGAGGCAUUCGGGCCGGUGGGGCGUAAGGGUUAUCGUUAAGCACAAGACACAGAAUAGUUUACACACUGUGUGGGGGACGGCUUCUCACGCUUUGUUUACUCUCUUCAUCCGUUGUGACUCUAGGCUUCAGGUUGCAUUGGGGUUCCUCUGUACAGCAAGAUGUUUCUUGCCUUUUGUUAAUGCAUUGUUGUAAAGUAUUUGAUGUACAUUACAGAUUAAAGAAGAAAAGCGCGUUGUGUAUAUUACACCAAUGCCGCCGUGUUUCCUCAUCUAUGGUUCUAAAUAUUGCUUCAAUUUCAAACUUUUGAAAGAUGUAUGGAUUUCCAGUUUUUCUUUACUUUCUCCCAGUAUGUUUUAACAAAAAAAAAAAAAAGCAGGAAAAAAGGAAUAUUUAGCAGUAUUGUUCGUUCUGAUAUGUGAAUUUGUUUGUGACAACUAAACAAGGCAUUCAGCAGUUUCUGACAAUUAACAUACAUCAUUCCACACUCCUUGUCAACAAAGUGCUUUUUCACUGCCUAAAAUUUUAGAUGUAGAUAUUUGAAAUAGAUUUUUUCAUUUAUACCAGUUUUCUUUAUGAUGAUACAGUGUUAAAAGAAAAUAAAUUACAAUUGAUCUGUCAUCCAUAUUUGCUAAGAAUGUCUAUUUCCAAGAACCUAUAUCUUACAAAAUACACAUUCUUGCUUGUGUGUCUGUGUGUGUGGGUGUAUGUAUGUCCACGUACUAGAAAAAUUACCUGUGUGAGAUUUUAUUUUGACAGAAGCUAUUUCAUUUGCUGUUCAUCUUGUACAAACUUUGUUUUUGGUUUUUUAGUAUAAAUGUACAUCAGUUUGUUCCUUUUGUACUGUAUCUAUUCUUCUGACCAUCUAGUGACUCAGGAUAUUAGGCCAGUUGAAGUGGAGUUAUAGGAUUUUCACACAUUCACGCAUACUUGGAUAUCAACCCUCUCUACAGGUCCGUUUCCUUACACAUUUUAUCCCCUCAGAACACGAUAAACCAUGGCCAAUUCAGUUUCACUUUGGGGCCAAUUACUUGAAGUAUCCACAGAAAAUGUAAACUGCUCGCCUUAUUCCCCCAAACUUUUUGUUCAUGUGGCAGGGAGCAGUACACAACUAUGGAAUAGAUUAUUAAAACUGAACUUGAAGCUAACGUUAGAAUAGUGGUUAACAGAGCUAAGAAAUAAGGCUAACCAUCGAAAAGAACAUGGGCCGCGGGUAAACUAGCUUUGCUCUUUAGAUGCAAGUGGCUGAGGCCAAUAGGUGCCUAGUAAAUGUUAACUGUUCUUGGAAAAAAUAAAAACAUCAGUAACAAAAGAAA